ACUCAGCCUCCCUUCCCCAGCCGUGACAGCACUGGAGCCUUUCGGACACCUGGACCAUGGACCCCAGGGAAUGUGUCUGCAUGUCUGGAGGAAUCUGCAUGUGUGGAGACAACUGCAAAUGCACAACCUGCAACUGUAAAACAUAUUGGAAGAGCUGCUGUCCCUGCUGCCCCCCGGGCUGUGCCAAAUGUGCCCGGGGCUGCAUCUGCAAAGGAGGCUCAGACAAGUGCAGCUGCUGCCCAUGAAAGCCAUCCAUCGUGCCCACCCCUU